ACAUUUGUGAUCACCUGGUCACACACCUGGGCAGGAGGCUGCCCCUCCCUGGUUUGAGGAAGCAGGAAAAGGUACCCGCGAGAGACAGCCAGCAGUUCUGUGGAGCAGCGGUGGCCGGCUAGGAUGGGCUGUCUCUGGGGUCUGGCUCUGCCCCUUUUCUUCUGCUGGGAGGUUGGGGUCUCUGGGAGCUCUGCAGGCCCCAGCACCCGCAGAGCAGACACUGCGAUGACAACGGACGACACAGAAGUGCCCGCUAUGACUCUAGCACCGGGCCACGCCGCUCUGGAAACUCAAACGCUGAGCGCUGAGACCUCUUCUAGGGCCUCAACCCCAGCCGGCCCCAUUCCAGAAGCAGAGACCAGGGGAGCCAAGAGAAUUUCCCCUGCAAGAGAGACCAGGAGUUUCACAAAAACAUCUCCCAACUUCAUGGUGCUGAUCGCCACCUCCGUGGAGACAUCAGCCGCCAGUGGCAGCCCCGAGGGAGCUGGAAUGACCACAGUUCAGACCAUCACAGGCAGUGAUCCCGAGGAAGCCAUCUUUGACACCCUUUGCACCGAUGACAUCUCUGAAGAGGCAAAGACACUCACAAUGGACAUAUUGACAUUGGCUCACACCUCCACAGAAGCUAAGGGCCUGUCCUCAGAGAGCAGCGCCUCUUCCGACGGCCCCCAUCCAGUCAUCACCCCGUCACGGGCCUCAGAGAGCAGCGCCUCUUCCGACGGCCCCCAUCCAGUCAUCACCCCGUCACGGGCCUCAGAGAGCAGCGCCUCUUCCGACGGCCCCCAUCCAGUCAUCACCCCCUCAUGGUCCCCGGGAUCUGACGUCACUCUCCUCGCUGAAGCCCUGGUGACUGUCACAAACAUCGAGGUUAUUAAUUGCAGCAUCACAGAAACAACAACUUCCAGCAUCCCUGGGGCCUCAGACAUAGAUCUCAUCCCCACGGAAGGGGUGAAGGCCUCGUCCACCUCCGAUCCACCAGCUCUGCCUGACUCCACUGAAGCAAAACCACACAUCACUGAGGUCACAGCCUCUGCCGAGACCCUGUCCACAGCCGGCACCACAGAGUCAGCUGCACCUCAUGCCACGGUUGGGACCCCACUCCCCACUAACAGCGCCACAGAAAGAGAAGUGACAGCACCCGGGGCCACGACCCUCAGUGGAGCUCUGGUCACAGUUAGCAGGAAUCCCCUGGAAGAAACCUCAGCCCUCUCUGUUGAGACACCAAGUUACGUCAAAGUCUCAGGAGCAGCUCCGGUCUCCAUAGAGGCUGGGUCAGCAGUGGGCAAAACAACUUCCUUUGCUGGGAGCUCUGCUUCCUCCUACAGCCCCUCGGAAGCCGCCCUCAAGAACUUCACCCCUUCAGAGACACCGACCAUGGACAUCGCAACCAAGGGGCCCUUCCCCACCAGCAGGGACCCUCUUCCUUCUGUCCCUCCGACUACAACCAACAGCAGCCGAGGGACGAACAGCACCUUAGCCAAGAUCACAACCUCAGCGAAGACCACGAUGAAGCCCCCAACAGCCACGCCCACGACUGCCCGGACGAGGCCGACCACAGACGUGAGUGCAGGUGAAAAUGGAGGUUUCCUCCUCCUGUGGCUGAGUGUGGCUUCCCCGGAAGACCUCACUGACCCCAGAGUGGCAGAAAGGCUGAUGCAGCAGCUCCACCGGGAACUCCACGCCCACGCGCCUCACUUCCAGGUCUCCUUACUGCGUGUCAGGAGAGGCUAACGGACAUCAGCUGCAGCCAGGCAUGUCCCGUAUGCCAAAAGAGGGUGCUGCCCCUAGCCUGGGCCCCCACCGACAGACUGCAGCUGCGUUACUGUGCUGAGAGGUACCCAGAAGGUUCCCAUGAAGGGCAGCAUGUCCAAGCCCCUAACCCCAGAUGUGGCAACAGGACCCUCGCUCACAUCCACCGGAGUGUAUGUAUGGGGAGGGGCUUCACCUGUUCCCAGAGGUGUCCUUGGACUCACCUUGGCACAUGUUCUGUGUUUCAGUAAAGAGAGACCUGAUCACCCAUCUGUGUGCUUCCAUCCUGCAUUAAAAUUCACUCAGUGUGGCCCAGA